AUAACCUUGACCAAAAUAUGAUGAAAGAUAACCUUUGCCAAAAUAAGCCUUAAAGUCAGCUGUGGCAAGGUUUUCUCCUGUGACAUUUCAAAAAGUUGUAGGAAGAUUACCUUGAGCCUCUUCAAAAUAACCUUUCCUUUUACAUGUUGAUGACUGAAAAUCAUAAGCUGUAAGGCUUUGUCUCAAAAAGUUCACAGUGUUCCAGUGUUCCUGUAACAGGGAGAAAGGGGAUUGAUUUAACUCAUUAAACGUUUUCUAAUCUAACAUUUGCUUUUGAAAAUUUGCAGAAUUUUCAGAUCUUUUACUAAAACCUGAUUUAGUUAGGGGUGAAGACAGAGACCUAAGCCUUCAGUGCCCGGUUCAAAAAGGAUUUUUCACCAAGAUUCAAAAAUCUUAUUGAAUCAGGGAAAUGCAAAAGAAAUUGUAUCUAUUUUAGUUUUACCUACUAUAAAUAAUUUAUAGAUAUCAUCAAGAAUUUAAGCAGGAUAGUUAACUAUACAAUUAUGACAGCAUAUUUAUUUUAUUAAAAAACAGUGUUAAAAGUAAUGUCCAAGGUAACAUUUACAUUUGCAAAGGAAUGGAACCAUGGACUACAAUUACAAUUAAUGGCUAGGCAGUUGUUUUUAAUUUGCUUAAAAUAAUUCAUGUUUUAAAGGUGUACUGUGUUCUUAAGUAAGAUUUUUUUUUUUUUGCCUUGAGACAGAAAAAUAUUUUUUUCUCAUAAGAAACAUUGGUAUACUUCUGUAACAUUCGCUAGGGAAACUUUGGUAUAUCCAGUUUUUCAGGAAUAUUUGUUUCAGGCCCAUCAAUUUGGAUUCAAAACUAAACCCCUUAUAUAACUUAUUGCCAUGGCUGAAUACUUACAAGCUACAAUUUUAGUUUACCCCAAUUUAAGCAAACUUGAUGAAUGAAUUCGGAUAUAAAGGUAUAUAAAUUAAAUUAUAUACUUGACAUAUUUGCCAUAGGAUUCCUUGGAAGAGCAGCCUUUGCUAGUUGGUAUAAAAUGAUUCAACGUAGAUGCAAAUUUACAGUUUUGCAAAGAAGUACACAAAUGAGUAAGCACAUAAUUAGUGGGAUACUACUGUUUUUCAAAUGCAAACAUGGCUGAUAAACAUCUCUCCUUUCCUCAUUAGUAUCCACGUCUUGUUAUGAUAGUUACAAUAUCUUGAAAUUUGCUGUAUUGCAACUGAAACUGGAAGGGCAGGUUGAAGCAUAAGUGGAUGGUUAGGUGAUCUCUGAUGUCUUGCAAAAUAUUAGGGGUUUUAUCCCAGUAAACACCAGCUUAGUCAUCAUUUGGUUAAACCAUAUAAAUUUAUCUUUUAGUCAUUUCAUAAUUGAGGUUUUCAUGGUUCCCAGGAACUUCUCUCUCUUUUCUGUAAUUUGCCUUUAAAACUGAUAUAUAGAAAACAAAAUCACACAUUGCAGUUGUUUAUUAUUGACCGGCUACAUAUAUUUAACAACCGAAGGAAAAUAUGUAAUUUCAAAUAUUAUUUGUAGUUUAAAGUGCAUCUAAUUUAGGAAUACAGUAGGAAUUAGAUCAUUAACCCACAAAAAGUCUCAUAAAGGUCUUUACAAAAGACAAGGAAAGGUAUUAUUCUAGAAAGUGACUUGUUCCAGAGAGAUACAUCAUUUGGGUACCAUAAAGAUAAAUGUACAUGAAUGGAAAGAAACUGUGAAUCGUGAAGACUGAUGAGAAAGAUGAGUGAACAGGAGUCUCCCCUGGAAUCAGAAUCCUUGGAGCUAGAACAUCUGGUAUGGGAGAUGGUGAAGAGCAUAGCAGUGCGGGCCACAAAUUGGGGAUUUCCAUGUCUCAUCAUUGUUCCUCUGUGGCUUCCCAUCCUUCUUGCCAGGCCAAGCAUGAUAGUUUUUAGUUGCUAUUGGAGGUGGCAGAAAUGGUUUAUAAACUUUGAUUUUUGUAACAUUGCUUGAAAAGAGUCAUUUUUCAAGUGUAAUUCAUACACUUAAAAUGGAAAUACACACUCAUGUAAAGAUAUGUACUGUAUUCAUCAUUUAAAUUUUUAACCUGGUACAUAUGUCUCCAAAAAAAGGAUUGAAUGAAUGGAUUCAAAGGAGAGAAAUUCCAUUCUAUCAUUCUACCUGUCAGUUUAACCCUCUUGAUGUUGAUUUAAUGUAAGGUAAACAUCGUACAUUUUAUAAACUCUAUGAGGAAAUAGAAACAGUUUACAAAUUUUUCUAAAAUAAUUGGCUUAAACAGGAUAUUGGGAAAUUAUAAAAUACUGAUGUCAAAAUCUUUCCUAAAAUGUCUUAAUUUCAUUUCCUGUUAGUUUUGCAGAGGGAGGAAUGUCAAAUUUCCAAACACUUUUGUUUGAAACUAAUUCUCUGUGUAAAAUCAAAACUUGAAGAGAGUUCGCCUCUGCACCAGAUGAAUUUGUGGUUAAUUAUAUUAUUAAAUUGUUAAUAAGAUCCAGUUGUUCAGAAGUAAUAUAUUCUUAAUUUCAUUGAGGCAAAACAAAUAUCCAAAAAUAUUUUCAUUUAAUUUUGGAUUUUGUUUUAUUUUGUUUUUUUGCAACAGAUUUGCCUUCCUCACCAUACUUGCCUGGCUCUAACAUUAGAAAAUAGUCAAGAUCUUUAAAAGGCUCAUGCCAACAAAAAGUGAAUGAGGAAGUAGGCCAGGUGUGUGUGGUUAUGGUGGGAUCAGAAGUAAGGAGCCAAUCCAAGAUUUCAGGAUUAUCUGUAGGUGAUCCCCAAGGCAGAUAAUCUACUUAUGAACUGUGUGAGGCAAUGUAGGCAACGACAGUGAUGUCAGGGAAGAAAGAAAAACCACCUACCUGCCUAAGACCUGACAAAACUGUGCUUCGUUUUCAUGUGGUUGCAUGGCAAAAUCUAACAAUGAGAUAAAAAAUCAAGUCUAUCAUUUUUGAGAAUUUUAUUAUUUCUAAAAAGAGUAUUAAGUAGGAGAAUAUUUUGACAUAACUGGAAAUGUUGCAUCAUGAAGAGUGUUUUUAACGUCUGAGGCAAAGGGAGAAUGCUGAUUAAAUGUGCAACUUGAGCACAGGUGUUUAAUACUUGUUCUCUCCCAAAACAAAGGAACAUGAAGUGAAGAACAAAUAGGGUACAGACUCUUAACAGACAGGAGAGUGAGAUCGCAGAAAAUGAAAGAUAUUAACAAAUCUCUGGAAUAAGUUAUGGAAAUUUCAAACCUAAUUUAAUCAGUUUUCAACAGAAUGGAGCUAUAGUGAGGAUGACAUGCCAGUAUUAAAAACAAGAGUCCUGUGAAAGUCAAAACCCCCAAAGCCACUUGGUUUUGGGGUGUUUGCUGGCCAGGCAUAACUCCUAUAGGCAGGAGGAUUCCUUUUUGGAAAAAUGCUCCCCACCCCCCCAAAAAAGAUCUGUAGAUACAACAUUUGAGGGUCCUCUAAUAAACCAGUAGGCCAGUAGGCUUCCCAGGUGACCACGUUGCAGUGAAAUUAACCAGUCAACAAGCCCCUUUCAUGCACCUGAAACUUCCAUCUGAAUUUUAGUGUUUUCCUCUUAAAUGAGAACUGGCAACCAAGCGGCCUCAGACUUGUGAGGAAUGUCCAUGAUAUGACAGUUAGGAACAAACCACAAACCAGAAAAGAAGAAUCUUGGAAGAAAUACCAUAUAGGAACCAGAAAAAAAGUUCCUUAAUUGCUUGAAAGGGAUCAGAGAAUAGAGGAUAUAUAUAUAUAUUUUUUAAACAGGAUUUUUUUUUUCUUUAAGAAGCAGCUGGAAACUAAAAAUUGCAGAAAUAAAUCCAGAAUGAUUGGAUGGCUGAAGGGGAGGAACUUUCCCAGAAAGUCAAAAUUUUCAAAAGGAGAAAAGGUAAGAUAGGAAAGGAAGAAAACAAAUUAGAGAAUGUCUCCAUGAGGAUCAACAUUUAAGUAAUAGAUGUCCCAGAAAAGGAAUAGAGGCGAUCAUUUUGUACAUUGUAUAGAUAGAGGUGAUUCUUUUUAUUUAUUCAAUUUUUUAUUUAUUUAUUUAUUUAUUUAUAUUUAAGAGACAGGUUCUUACUUGGUUGCCCAGGCUGGAGUGUGGUGGUGCAAUCACAGCUCACUGCAGCCUCAAACUGCUGGGCUCCAGCCAUCCUCUGUCCUCAGCCUCCCAUGUAACUGGGACUACAGGCAUGUACCACCACAUCCAGCUAAUUUUUUAAAAAAACUUUUUGUAGAGACAAACUCUUGCUAAGUUGCACAGGCUGGUCUCAGUUGUUCCUCUCGCCUCAGCCCCCCAAAGUGCUAGCAAGGAUCUUUUUUUUUAUAAAAGAGAAAACUGAUAGAUCACAUGAUGUCCUCAACCAUAUUGAGACAGGUUUUAUGCUUUGGAUUAACAAGAAUUUGUGAUAGUUACGUUAAAAACAAAGCAACUGUAAAAGUAAGGCAGUUACUCACCCCAGGCUGGGGAGUGGGGGCAUUGCACAGGAAAGGAUAUAUAAUCCAUUUGGCUCCACUGUGAACUGUAUAGUAUAAACUGAAUUUUUAUUAUAAUCCCCAAACUGUGAUAGGCCAAAUUGGGAGGAUCGGGGAGGGAGAAUGUGGAGUGUGAGUAUAUGCGGUGUGAUAAGCUUCCUACAUAAUGGAAAAUCAGUAGAUAAGAUAUACAAGUCAUUCAUAUUUAGAAACAUGGAGACAAGUAUCAACAGAAACUGCUCCAAGAGUUAGAAAUACACACCUCUAGGGAGAAGGAAUCAGGUGGGAGGUAUGGGGCAUGGGCUGCUGGUUUUCUUUUAUUAAUUAUAAGCCUUUUAAUACCAUCUGAUUAUUAAAACCAUGGGCAUAUUUUAGUUUGACUUAAAACUAAAGCAGGCAGCAUAGUUUUUUGCUUUUUUCAAAACCUACCACAUACAGUUUUGAAAUGGCACACAAAUAUCACAGUAUGAGAGUUGUAAACUGCACAGCUGAGGAUGGCUGACGGGUUCUUCCAGUGAGGUGUGGGUUCACAGGUGAGCAUCCCGUGCAGUGAACAGGACCCAGCACUUGGUUUAAUACUCUGCUGUCGCCGUUUUGAAAUUCUUAAUAAUUUAGGCACAAGAGAGAACCCACGUUUUCGUUUUGCACAGAACCCUGCAAAUUAUGUAGCCAGGCCUGCUUCUAAUAGAUACAUUGUUUGGAUUCUAGCCUGAGUGAGGUUGCUACUACUUCCUUUGACCCUGACCUCCUAGUGGCCUGCUGUUUUCACCACUCACAUAUUGAUAAGGCCACCAGGAUUGACGUAAACCGACAUUCCCUCACGAGGGAAUUUGGAAGUCAUGUAUUGCAUGAUACCGUAGAAAGUUGUUACGGUGGCUUCUAUGGGUUAAUUCUGUGUCCUUUUAAGGAAGACAUUUGGUGUGGGAAAAGGUUAUUUUUAAUUCUAAUUAAUUAUGUACUGAGGGAAAUGGUUUUCACAGGAAAGAAUAUCAAUACUUCACAACAGAGAAGUGGAGAGCUAAGCUUGCAGCACCCUUUUGGGGGAGAGGAAGAAGCUUAGAUCGUUGUCCAGAUUGGGAAGUCUGUGGUGGCCCUGAGGUGUGAGGAGACCCCGGUGAAUGAGUACACAGAGAGAACUAAAAUCUGGCCCCUUUUGACAACCUGAAGCCCUCACUUGACCUCCUGUAAUGAGCUAUGUCCCCUGCAGGCAGUUCCCUUCCCCUGCAGGGGGCAUAUCUCAUUGGUCACUGCAUGGCAGACUGGGAGUCCCACCUGUGAGAUGGGGAAGGCGUCAUGGGAAGCACACAAGCCGGGUGUGCUCUCCGAAAGGGUCCCCUGUGAAAGCCUCCGUGUGGGGUGGGAUGUCAUUGAAGCUUACUCGGGGUGGGGGGUGGGCUCAGCUGAGUAAGUCACAUAGAGAGAGGGAGGGGAUAGACGGUGCUAACUAAGGGGUAAUAGCUUGUCACCCUGAAGUGAGGAGGCAGGUUUUCUUGUUUGGUUAGUAAAGUAAUUUUAAAGGCAGUUACCAAAGAGGAACCUUAGAAAUAUCUAGAGUAACAAUAGUGUAUGAGUAGUCAUUGCACAGCCCCCUGCCCACAUGAUGUAAUAGAAUUCAAGGCACCACUAAUUCGGGUAUGUGUGUUCUGCUGUUUUUCUUAAGUUAUUUAUAGUUAUAACUUAUUUAUUCAUUACAAUUAUUUAUAAUUGCAGUGUUCCAGAGAUAGCUGUAUAGCUAUGUUUAGUAUAAGGAAGCAUUUGUCUUAGAUAAAAUUUUUUCUUUUCCUGUUUUGCAUUUUGGAUAAAACAGUUUUAUAAAGGAUGAAAGUUUAUAAAGGAUAAAACAGUUUUAUAAAGGAUGAAAGCUCCAAUGCAAGUAACAUUAACUCAGGCAUGCCUGGGAGUGCUAGGAAGAGCUGAUGCAACAAUCAGAGCCUUCCUUCUUCCCAGUCUGUAAUGGCUUUUGCUAUCCCUUCGGGUCCUGUGCCCAUCACUGUGCUAGACAGCAGAGAUAGAGGGCUGAACACAAAUCAAGUGUCUCUGUCAUUGGAGAGCUCACGGUCCAGAGAGAGUGAGAGGCUAAGCACUUGCACAUUGAGAUAAAGGUAGCACGUGAAAAGUUCCAGGUGUCUUGAGAGUUUAAAAGGAGAAGCUACUUGAGGUUGAGUUCAGGCAAACCUUUUUUAAAAAAUUUAUUUAUUUUUAAUUGAGACAGGGUCUCGCUGUGUUGCCCAUGCUGGUCUUGAACUCCUGGGCUCAAGUGAUCCUCCUGCUUCGGCCUCCCAGAGUGUUGGGAUUACAGGCAUGAACCGCUGUGCCUGGCCAAGGCAAACCUUUUUGCGGAAUGACUUGUAAGCCGAAACCUGAGUAACAAGUAAGGAGGUAGUAUUGCAAGUACAGGGAACGGAGUGUGUGAAGGAUAUGAAACAAGAACAAGUUCUUUGUACGAAAGGAAUCCAGAGAGCCUCUGUGUCCCUACUCUCAGAAAGGAAGGGGCAGAGUAGCACGGGAUUGUGCUACGAAGGCUGUGGGGCCAGAGAAGCUAGGACCAAAACCUCCAUUAGGGAUUUUCAUUUUAAAAUUAUACAUACAAUGGAAAGCCAUUGAUUGCCAUGGUUGGGGGUGGAGGGUGGCGGUUAAACAGCAGAACUUGAAGUCCUGGAUCUUCAAAUAUCAUCAUAAUGAUGGUCCUCCUAGGAGACAGUUUUCACACUUACUGAAGGUUUUUGGAUUUGUCAGAUUAAGGUGGAUUUGAAUCCCAUUUCUCUUGUUCAUUGUGUGGCCUGGGACAAAUGACUUAAUUCCACUGAGUCUCAGAUUUCUACCUUGUAAAAUUGGUGUGAUAAUACCAUAUGUCAUAGGGGAGAUUGAAGGAUAUAUGAUAUAUAAGACACUUGUACAGUAUCUGACAUCUAAUAAGUUUUCAAUAUAUGAUAGUGAUGGGAGUAGUAGUUGUUGAGUUUGUUAUUAUUAUGUAUUUAGGACAUUAAACAGGUGUUAAUGGACAGAGGAGCAGAAUAAUAAAUAAUUAACCUAUUGGGUCAUUAAAUAGGAGAGGGAUAUAUCAAAGAAUUUGUUCUAAGAAUCAAAGAGAGGAGCUAAAAAAUGAUAUUUGUUUGUCUUUGUGAUAGCGAAAGUCAAAAAGCAUAGCAGUAAAAUGUGAAUAAUUUCACUCCUUUUCCUCCUGGGUGUUUUUACUUUGUGGAGUUGUAUGUAAGAGUUCAGAAAACAAACAUGGAGUGACUGGUCAUUAGACAUAUUCAAAUAUUCCUGGUAUAUAAUUAUCAGUGCAUUUUGAAUUACUCAUUUUCUCAAGGAAAAGUUUUUGGAGACUUUAACUUUUUUAGAAAUGGGAAAAAAAUGCUAACCUGACCUGCUUCAUGGUGAUUCAUUCCUUUCUCAUUUUGCUCCUUAAAACAAACCAAGAAGCCAGAUGUUUAGUUGCCUAAGAUGAAAGCUGUUUCCUUAGAAAUCCUGAAUGAAAGAAAAACUGCUUCUCUAGAAUGGCAAAGUCCAUUUAGGAGGUAAUCGUGACCUGAUUUAGGCAAUAGAAUGUGGUUGAAAAAUGUUGCUCAUAGCAACCAAGAACACUUGUAGAUAAAUUAGUUUUCUAAAAUAAGCCUUCUCUAAUAACUGUAUAUGGAAUUUUCCUGUUCAACUGUACUGUGCAUUCUUUUUUGUCCAAUGAUUGUAUUGACCUAAAUAGUUCGGUUUGGUGGGCUUAUAACCUUUUGAUUACAUCCAUUUGCUUAAAAAUCUUCCAUUUCUUUUAUAGAAUGUUUUUCACCUGUCAACAUACUCUUGUUCUUUCUGUGAAUUUAUAUAAAAUGUAAUGGUGUCAAGGUACUAGAAAAAAGUCCAAGUUCCCCCGUAUUUAUAAACAGCAGACUGAAAUUGGUAAUUUUUAAUUGUCAUUACUUAAAAAGAUAAAAAUGAAAUAAACUUCUAGUAUGUCUGAUUUUUGUUUCACUCUUUUUAGUGAUGAAACAUUGAGCAUAAAGCUCUGAAACAUGAGUGUAAAAUUAGUAUUUUGACCACUUUUCUCUCUACUCUUGAUUCCUUAAGUAAAAUUUAUGAAUAUCAUAAAUAGAAAUCUAGAUAAAAUAGUCAUGUGUAAAAAUGCAUCGACUCCAAAUAUGCAAAAAACCUUUCACAAAAUAAAAUUUUAUUUAUCCAUAGAUAGGGUUCUAGGCAGCAUUACUUCAUUAUUCACCAUAGGCCUCUUGCUUUGUGAGUUGUUUUUUAAAUAGGAAUUAGAUGUAGAUUUGUAAAAUUUUGAAACUCCUAGAUAGAUGUGGAAAAAGAAUACCAUAAUUAGACACAAGUUCUUCAAUAUCUAUAAUGAUCACAAGACUUUAAAAAAAUUUUUUUUCUUCCAUCUUGAUACCAUAGUUUAGGCCUGACCAGCUACCCUACUUUCAAAUUCUCAGCACAUUCUUUGAAAAGAUGGAUUAAAAUAUUAGUUUCCAUGCUAUAGAGAAAUGCCUGUGAAAAGUAAUUUUUUCUUCGGCAUAGGUACACAGCUGUUAAUCUCUCCUCCUCACUCAUUUCUAAUUUUUAUUCUUUUCAUCACCUGUAGAGAUAAUUUUGUAUAUGGAAUUUUCUGGAACAGAGUUCACUGACACAGUGGUCUCCAUGGUAAAUUUACCAUCAGGCAAAUACCGUCACUGCUUCUGACACUCCCUCUUCACUUAUUUGCCUGUGUCUUCUGGUUUCUUACAAAACAUUCAUUUAAACAGUCAAUAAAGAACAGAAACACUGGAGAUCAGAGGACUGGAAUUCCAGUGACUGCUCUGCUUCAUGACCUCAGCCACACCGCUUUUCCUCCCCGGGCCAUGUUUAGCCAGUGGAGGGAGUUGACCCCACUGUCUCUGCCGUCUCUUCUAGCCCAUUCUGGAUGAUCAGAAUAUUCAAUUUUGCUUUUGCGGAGAAGUUUUAGAGAGGGGGAUUGUAGCUUGUUUCUCUCCUAGCUUCAAUGUGUUGUUCAAAUUUUAAAUUUGUAUCAUAGAUGAAAAAGAAACACUCAUCUGGGAGUGCUGGUGGCAUUUGGAGUUAAUUUUGGACUCUUCUGAUGAAAACUCCAGUUCUAACCAUAGCCUAUCUCCCCUUUCUCUUAACAUGUAUUCAGUCAAGUAACAAAGAUUUAUUGACCUAUGUGCCAGACACUCUUUUUGGCACUGAAAUCCAAUAUAUUAUAUAAUACAGUUGUCUUAAAGUUGGCAACUCUAUCUUGAAAGUAUGAUGCGUUCAUACUUUCAAACUAAGUUAUUAUUAAUGUUUAGAAGUGUACACAAAAGCUAUGAACUUCUUUCACAUAAUCCUUUCCUAAUUUUGUUUUGCGUAUGAUAUAAAAUAUAAAUGAGGAACAGAUAAACCACAACCUCUGGUACUAAAGUAUUCUUUUAUAUUUGCUGCUACCUUGUAAUGCUCAUGAAUUUGUCAGUUUAGAUUUUCAAAAUUAUUUAUGUAUGUUAUCUGUGGUUCCUUUGGUUUUACUAAUACUCAUCAAUUCAUUUCUUAACAUAUACCAAUAGGGCAUCUUUUAUUUGUAAUCAUCUAUUUCUAAUUAAUCAACUUGUUCAGAGAUUUUAUAAUCUAAGGACAAAACCUUGUUUUCUUGACUUUGAGCAUUUUAGUUCUCCCUUCUCUUCCUUUCCCUUCCUUCUCUUCUCCUUCUUCCUAUUAAGUCUUCCCCAGAUUUCUAUCAAUUCUAAAUCAUAAAGGCCCAGGUUCAACUUUCUAGUAUUUCCAUAUACUUGUAGAACAGCAUAGAAUUAUUUCAUGAAACACCUUAGAAUUCACCUGCCAGUGGUGGUAUGAUUGUAAUGAAGUCAAAAUGAUUAGCCAUUUUCUCCUUUUAUGACUCAUCUUUGUCUCCUUAUUCUUCAUCUGUUGGUAAACUUUAAGUUAUUUUUAAUGUACUUUUACCUAAUGUAACUCAGAAGUCAAAGCCCAUAGGUAAAGAAGGCCCUAUUAUAGUUAAAGCAAGAAAUUCAAUACUUUAGGCCAGUUACUUGAGGACUUAUAAAAGUGUGACAAAUUAUUUUAACCCUUAUAGUUGGGCUAAGGUUAAAAGCUGGCUGUACAUUAACAAAAUAGCUAUUAGGUAAGUAAACAGUGGUCUGAGAGGCCAGCUAGACAUUGAGUAGCUGCCUUGUUCAGAUGGAAGUAUUGUUGCUAAGAAAUAAAAGUAGGAUCGAGAACUUGGAGGCCAUACUACUGUGUCCCCUAUGCUCAGAAAACACAUGGCCCACAAUAUGCCCUCAAAAGAUAUUUGUUGAAAAAUAUGUUUCUGACUUUGUUAUCGUCUGAUUAGAACUUUUGUACAUUUCUUUAUGUGUGGACAUUUAAAAAUAUUAAUGUAACAAAAAUGGACUAAGGUCAGUGAUAAAAGAUAUAGGUUCUCAUUCUAAAUAGAAAAUCACAUAACUUACUUAUCUGUUAACGUCUGACUUAUCUAAAAAUUCAGUCUGCUAACCAUGUAAUCAGGGUAUGGAAAUUUGUAAUUGAAAGAUUGUAUGAGUUGGCCUCUCAUUAAUAAAAAAUUGACUCCUUUGUUGUUUAUAUUUUAUGUCUGUUGUGUUAUCUGUUUAUGCCACUUCCAUAUUAGUACUAGUUCUAGAAGGGAGGCAUUGAGAACUCCUCUGUCCCAUGGCCACAGCUGGGGAGUUUCCUCUUCUACAGACUCUGAAUCAGCCCAGAAUUCUCUCCCCUCUAGCCCCAUCCUCCUUAAACCCUUCUUCCAUGGAGAUUCUUUCCUUCUCUCAUAAUCACAGGUGUGGUCUUCACAGGUGUGAUCACAGGUGUUCCCAGCUGUGAUCUUCUUAAUCUGGUCCUGAGGAAAGAAAAGGUAAAUCAGAGAAAUGAGGGAAAAGUCCUCACUGGCCUACCCUAAACCCCCUGUCCCCUCUUUCUGUUCCACUUUAUCUCAAUUCAUUACCCUCAUCCACCUCCUCCCAAGUUCCCGUUUCAUUUGUCAUCCCCAAGCCCUUGGCUCUGUCCCUCACCUCCCAAAACUGUGGCCCUCUUAUAGGCUACUCUCCAUCCCCUCUCAUGGCAUCCACACCCCACAAAUCCCCAGGAGUGACUGUGAAAAGAUUCUGAGCUUACAAUGAAAGGAACAGGAUUCCCUGCUCAGGCCAGCGAGGCAGGAUGCUCUUGCCGCCCCAGGUGUCGCUGGCCACGGGAUGCAUUUUCCCCAGUGUUCUGAGUUACUCCUGGCCUUGUCUUAGUACUGUGUUUUAAAUCCAGUUUUGUGGGCUGAUCUGACAACUUAACCUCAAAUUUUAUUCUUGUUUCCCUGGGAAAAUAUUAAAAUUUUGCAGAACUGACUAAUAAAUGAACUUUUGGAAUACCAUAUGUUUGUAAAUGGGUGGCUGCCUGUUUUCUGAUAAUGGUGUAUCCUGUAGUGGCUCAGAAUGCCUUUGUUUGGGUUUGGAGGUGAAGAGAAAGAAAGGAUGUUUGGUUUGUUUUAACACUGAGAAUUUUUGGCUCUAAAAGUACUUUGUAAUCAUUUUAAUUUUUAUUAUUCUUUCAUUUAAAUUGGGACAUUUGUACCAAAAAUGUCUUUCAGAUUCAUGUAAUUCCUUAUAUCUAUCAACAGUUGUGUACCUAUGCUGAAGAAAAAAUUACUUUACACAGGCAUUUCUCUAUGGCAUGGAAACUAAUAAUUCUUUUCAAAGAAUAUGCUGAGAAUUUGAAAGUAGGGUAGCCGGUCAGGCCUAAACCUUGGUAUCAAGUCAUGCUGUGUAAAAGAUGGCUUUUCACAUAAUUGUUUUAGUGAUGUGUUCUGUCUGUGUAAGUAAAAAAAAAAAAAAGAGAGAGGGUAUUGCUUGAGAGAUAUUUACUUUUCCAUUUUUCUGUAUAUUUUUUAGAAUAUUUAUUAACCAGGUUAUCAGGACACUGUGUGUGUAGCAUCAUCCUAGAAGUAAUUAUCCACAUACUUCUCUUGGUUAAACUUAACUACAUGAAGUGUGUCCUCAGGAACUUAGCUGAACUGUGUGAAACCCAUUCAGUUCACACAGGCCCUUGAAUGUGCACUUUAAAGCUUUUCAUGGAAAAUGUCUGAACCUUUAUUAAUAUAUUGUUUAUAUCUGAAUUAAGUUAGGGCCAAGAACUGUAAUUAUUUUUCUCCUGCUUGCAUCAAUAGUUUUACAUAGGCCUUCUCUGCUGAUAAAUUUGAGUCAGAUUAAUGAGUAAUAAAUCUAAAGAUAACCUUUUAAAACCAUUGGAGAGCCAAGAAAGUGAACAUAUAAUUAUGAUUUAAAAGGAUAUGUGACUAAGGCACUCAGAUGUGUUUCAUCUGGUGCCUGGGUGUUCAUUUCUAGUUUUAACGCAAUUGAAUGAAAAUUACUUCCUAAUUCCAUCAAAAUAGCAUCAUUGGCUACUUUAGACUUUUUAGAGUUGAUGUUAGGAAAUACACCAGUACACCAUACAAAAUUAGAAAUUGAGGAAUCAGAAGGACCAGAAGUUCAACCAAAGGACUAAGAAAUAGUAAGUUCCUAGAAAAAUUCAAGUCAACUUUUUCUACAUAACAUUUUGCCAGUAUUUGUACUCUUCCUAAUUAAAAAUGGGCAUACCAUUUAAAAACAUACUGUAUUUAUCAAAAGUAGGAAUUUGUCUAAUAAAUUGAAAUUUUGUUUAAACAUCAUGCUUUACAUUCCUGAUAUGCCAUAAAACUUAAUGGUGGACCAGAAAUGUAAAAGCUUGACCAGUUGGGUUUCAUGUAUACUUUGAAACCAGAAGGCCAUCACUUGGUUGUUUGUUUCUACAGUAGAAAUGAAAACAAUUUAUUGUUUGCUAAAUAAUGGACACACUUUAAGAAUUUUAAAGUGAUUCGUAACCUUCAAGAGUUUACUUGGCAUGUACAGCUGUUUUUAAAAUUGCAUUGAAAUGCUGUUUUCAAAUAUCCUAGAGAGAAGGGGUCUUGUUUUUAGUCUGAAGCAAUAUCAGAUCACAUAUAUAGUCAGAAAUAUCAUAAGUUUGAGUAGAAAUGUUUAUCCUUCCUUCUACCUAACUUAAAUGCCUUUGGAUCUCUAUUUAAUGUGUUGAGAGACCCUGACUCUAUUUUUAAAGAAAUUGAGGCAAGAGUAUACUAAUAUUAGCCAAAAAUCCUUCAGUUGGAUACAUUAAAUAAUUUUAAGAAACCAACAAAAAAUCUAAUCAGUGCAUUGUAAUAGUAGUUGUAUUAAGGUUGAACUGUUAGAGGUGAUUUAUUUCUUAUUUUCCAAACUAUAAAGUGGUUAUAUUACUUUCAUAAAUAGACUUUUAAAAACAUGUCUCCAUGUGUAUAUAUAUUUAGAGAGGAGAGAGCCUCUGAAUGACUCAUUCUGGAAAAAAAGGGGGGCAGUUUUCAACUUUUCAAAUAGCUUUCUUUUCUCUUCUUCCCAUUUCUUCACUGAAAAUUGCCAGUUACUGUAUAUAAAAAGUGUUCCUUUUCUUUUAACCAUUUCUGCUUCCUGCCAAGGUGUAAAUCAGAAAGCCCAAGUUUCUUUCUCCCACUUCAUAAACAAGACUUCGUUCUGCUUCAGACACUUGGAGCCCUGCCAGAGUUGUCAUGAUGAUGUCAGUUUACCAAGAAUGUUCACAUUUCUCAUGCUGUGUUCCACAUUCCCUGGACUCGAGCAAAUGUCCUUUUAGAGCUCACUGAAGUUUCAGGAUUGGAUUUAAAAAGCAUGCCUUGUUUUCAGUACUUGCCCUUCAUGUGCUACCUUUUCAGAAUCAGGGAUCCAUUUUUAACAGCUUGACAGUUUACAAGCCCACACGAUACAUUUUGUAUUUGUCGAUUAAAUACAGAAUGACCAAAAGUUUAUCAGUUGGUGAAACCAGUCAGAUUUGCUAGUUUAACAAAUUGGAAUUUUAUUAAUAGUAUUCUCUCAUUUAGCAAGUAUUUAUUUUAUAUCUAUAUUUAUAAUUUAUGAUGUUUCAUUGAUUUUUUAAAUUUCCUUUUCACAAAUAACAAUGACAUCUACCUAUUUUGGGGGAAGUAAUACCUCUGUGUAGGAGAUGGAACUUAUCAGAUGAAUUCUGAUACCUUGUAUUAUUUCUUGAUUCUUGGCUAGCUGAUUGGAAACCACUAUGAUAUACAUCAUUGUAUCUAAUUAUUUAAUAAAUGAUUUGAGCCUGUAAGCCAUAAAUAUUAGAAAAUCCAGACGGUUUUUGAAACUUAUUUAGAGAGAUGGCUAUGAUUGAAGGGAGUAGUUGAACUUUGUGUAUACCUUGUCCUGGUAAAUUUAAUGGACAUCUCAUUUAUACAGAAGUUCAGAGGGCCAUGAAGAGUUCAGUCCUUCUAACAUUUAAAAUGUGUUGAAGCCCAAUUUUAUGGAUUUUUGUAGAACAAAGGUUUAAAAUAAAACCUGUUCUAUUUUAUAUCUGCUGCAUUUGAUCUAGUUAUCCCAUGUAAUUCAAUACUGUGCAGAAUUUUAUUUCUGAAAUGAUCCUUGAAAAUCAUAUAGUCUGACUAUAAUUUUACAGGUAAGUCUUGGAUAACUGAAUGAUUCUGGAUAGUUUUAACUACAUGUUCAGAAAAUUGGACUAAAUAAGAUAAAUUCUGUGAAAUAUAUUAGUCCUCAGAAUUCUUUGUAAAUGCCCAACAAAUAUGGAUGUGUUUAUAUGGAUUUAUUAUAGUAGUUGCACAUUGAUGACCUAAUUAACCUAAGAAACAAAAUAUCAGUACAUAAUUAUUUAUAUUAUAAACAUAUUUGAUUUUUUAAUAUCCUCUCAACUUGAGUUGGCAAAUUACAUCUUUACAAGGAAAGAAAGGGGGAAUUUUCUUGAUUUAUUUAUUUAUUUAGAGAUGGAGUCUCAUUCACUCAGUCACUCAGGCUGGAGUGCAGUGGCACGAUCUUGCUCACUGAAACGUCUGCCUCCCAGGUUCAAACGAUUCUCCUGCCUCAGCCUCCUCAGUAGCUGGAAUUACAAGCACGCACCACCACGCCCAGCUAAUUUUCGUAUUUUUAGUAGAGAUGGCGUUUCACCAUGUUGGCCAGGCUGGUCUCGAACUCCUGGCCUCAAGUGAUCUGCCCACUUCAGCCUCCCAAAGUGCUGGGAUUACAGGUGUGAGCCACCACGCCCAGCCUUGACUUAAUUUUAAAGUGGGCUUUGUUUGACUUUCUAGGCUGAUGUUGAAUAUUGCCUACUUUUCAUUUCUCUUAUAAUAAUAAUGUGAGCUACAGUUUUCUUUUAAUCACCAAGUUUUGAUUCACUCAAAAUAAUAGAACUUGAGAUGGGUGCCAGCCAAAACACUAAGUAUUGUUAAUCAUAGGCAAAACCCUGGUCCUCUGUCCUUUGUUCUCAUUGAGUGGCGUAAUGACUUGCUGAAUUCCAAUUCAUAAACUCAAAUCAUUGUGAAUUUUAUGUUUAAUCCUCCUAGCAUUGCUCUAUGGCAAAUGUAUCCUUUUGAUAAUUUUUAGAGCAUUCCCUUGCGGCUUUUUAUAGAAGUUUCAAAACAAGUUUAAACUAGGCAAAUUAAAAUCUAGUUUGAAUACAGAGAUUUUUAAAUCUCUAUUUUAAGAAAUAAUUGCAGAUUCCAAAAGUAGUUUUCAAAUUAGCAAGGAGGCCUCAACCAGUGUUUCAUUCCCAUUUUUGAACUCUUCAUCACAUUCUCUAGAAUUUCAAGAGUGAAUUUCCAGCGAGAAAAGGACCUGACACACGAGUGAAAUGGUUACCUGGCAUGAAAGGAUAUACAAGAUGGUCUACUAAGCCACAGUUGUACUGUUUUUGAUAUUACCAUUGUCUCUAUAUGGAUAAGAACUGUCUUAUAAACUCUGAUAUACUAUUUGUCCCACUUUUAUGCAUUGUAUAAAAUAAGUAAAUGUUUUGUUAAUUGACAUUGCUUUAGUCUUUCUGUAGUUUUGAGUUUAAGUUGUUGUGUGCAUCUUAAGGCAUUUCUCCAAGAAAUAUUUCCUAAUUGACCCAGUUUGCUUUAGGAAAGUUCCCUCAGUUCGCCUUUGAAAAGACUGUUUUUCUAAAUUUAGUGCUAUUUAAGAUUUCUUUUCUCUCCUUAUUUUCCAAUAUGAACUCCAGUUUCUUCCUUUGUUCCCAAGCAGCCAACUAGAGUAUUAGAGGGUCCUCCCUCAACCAGGACAUGAGAUUUAUUUCCUUUGCUGCAGAGCAGUGCUUUCCAUAGACUAGAGGUGCACUUAGUUUUCUUUUGUUUUUAUUUAUAAUUUUUAUUAUUAUUAUUUUGAGACACGGUCUCACUUUGUUGCCCAGGCUGGUCUCGAACUCCUGGCUCAAGUGAUCCUUUCACUUCAGGCUUCCAGAGUGAUGGGAUUACAGACAUGAGCGCCAUGCCAGGCCUUGUUUUUAUAAUGGUAUUGUUACUAAGACUUUAAUCUUUUAUUCUCUCAAGUAUUUCUUUUUUAUCCUUAACUAUCUUAAAAGUCACUUCCUUUUUUGUUGUAUGCACACAGCUAGCAUUUGAGGACACAGUGUAUGCAUAUUUCCAUAAAUUAAAGGCCCCAAACCUGGCUGUCUUGGGGAAAGUUUAUAUUCAGACUUCUCCAAAUUCUGUUUCCAAACAGAAAUGUAGUGUGAACAAAGCAGAGACUGAAGAGUGAAUUGCACUGAGUUGGUGCCGACACAGCGUCUCCUCUCUCCUCUUCAGCCCUGGUGACCGGCCUCUUUCCCUUUUGUAGGAAGUUCUUUUCAGAUCAGUAGCUGUCUGCAAGGCCUGUUCUCCCCUGCAGUUCAACUCUACUUUGUAAACAUUCUUUCAACGUUAGGUUUGUGUUUUGGAACCUUAUUAAAAGUUUUUGAAUCAGAUUCUCUCUUAAGUUCUCCAAAAUCCAGUGAUUCUGCACUGCUUCCCUUUCAAUGUCUGACACAACUAGGAGUAGUAAUUCAGUUGUUUUUCUGAUUCCCAUAACAUUAAUGCAUAAAAACAUAAGCAGAACAGUAAACCAUUUGUUCUCCUACCCUGAAGGAGAGCCCAAAUCCUUUGGUUGUAUUGGAAUUUUAUUUUCUAUGUGGUGUGAAACAAACCAAUCAUCGAACCCAUGCUUGGUCACCUUUUUAAAAUAACAGUUUACCUAUAAUAAUAUCUAUUGCUUUAUAAGAGGAUUCACUUUAUAUUGAUGAAACAUUUGCUAAACACUUAAGGAAAUUCCCAUAAAAUGAUGGUCCAAUUGUAAUGGUAGUUUAUAUUGGUCAAUAAUUUUAUUUUAUGUGAGAGUAUCUUGAAAUAUUUGUAUUUAUUACAUUUAAAAUUAUAAAUUUGCUUGAUUUUUGCCUUUUUCAGUUAUGUUUAUAAUGAAGCAAUAUGUUGAUGUUGAUCUUGUCAACUUUUGAUAAACAUGGCAAUUUACAUGGGAAAUGUAUUCUAUCUUAAAUAACCAGACAUGUGAAGAGACAAGAUAAAAUGAUUAUUUUAUAAAAAAUAAAGCAACAGGCAAUAAAAACAGACCACAAAGGAGCCAAAUUAUGAAGUUUUCAGACACAUGUUGUAAAGUAACUAUACGUGAUAUAUUCAAGUAGUUAAGACUGAGUUUAGUGGAGAACUUGAAACUGAAAAAAAAAGAAAUUCUAGACCUUAGCUCGUCUUUUUAUUCUUAAUUGUCUUAAAAUUCACCUUACGAUAGUUAAUGAUAAAAAGUUAAAACCAGCCCAAAGUGUGAUAUAAAAUAAACUUAAUAUCACCUUAAUAGAAAGCAUAUUUACUGUUUAGACCGUCAAGAUGAUUAACUGCUGCACCAUCAGUAAUCUGCUUUUGACCAGCUGGACCCUUUUUCUGACCACCCAUUUCAACAGUGCCAUUAUCACCCAGUUCUCAGAUCCAGGUCAAGUUGCCCCAAUGUCGCUUUCAUCAGCUUAGCGAUGUGAAUCCCAGCCAGAAAUUCAUCAGUUGCUUUUCAUUCUAAGAGUCAAAUAAGCAUUUGCUUGUUUGGGCAGAUUUGACCAGAAACUGGCAUUUUCUUUGCUUAUUGCCAACUUAACCAAAUUAUCAUUGCCUUAUCAAGGUUGUAGAGAGAGGACUUCUUUAAAGUUUUCCUAUUUUUUUACUCUACUUGAAGAACUUGGUGCAGGUUCAAAUGGAAUUAAUUUGAUCUUUAUCUAAUUUAUAUCAUAAGGUUUUGUUCUCGUAGUUUAUCAUUGAAUGAUGUUUCUGUCAAUUAAAAUUUUUUGCCAAAUUUUAGUUUGGGUUUAGAUUUCAAAAAUGUAAUUAUAUUUCAAAAAUGAAAUAUGAUUGGAGAAGACUCCCUGUGCUAUAUUGGUAAUACUGGUUUCCUAACAGUGGUCUUUCUAGUACAUAGAUAUGUCACUAGUUUGUAGUUGUUUUAACCAUUUCAUGAAUGAAAUCUUUAUGAUUAGUCUAUCCUUUGGAGAAUUGAGAGCUAACUGUACUAUGCCUGUAUUUGAUUUGCUCAUACAUUUUACUUGUCUGAUUUACUUAUAGACUGCAGACUGUUUUUUGUUGUUGUUGUUGUUUGGUUUUUGGUUUUUGUUUUUGUUUUUUUCGAGACUGAGUCUUGCUCUUUCGCCCAGGCUGGAGUGCCGUGGCACAAUCUCGGCUUACUGCAACCUCCGCCUCCCUGGUUCAAGCAAUUCUCCUCCCUCAGCUUCCUGAGUAGCUGGGAUUACAGGCAUGCGCCACCAUGCCUGGCUAAUUUUUUUGUAUUUUUAGUAGAGACAGGGUUUCACCAUAUUGGCCAGGCUGGUCUCAAACUCCUGACCUUGUGUUCUGCCCGCCUUGGCCUCCUGAAGUGCUGGGAUUAUAGGCGUGAGCCACCGUGCCCGGCCUACAGACUGUUUUAUUGGAGACUAUUCAUCAGCUUUCUGACCUGACACUUCAUUAUUACAAAUUUUAUAUAAAUACAUACAUAUGUUUUAUCAUUCGACAGUGUUUAUUUUGAAAAUUGUUUUUUGUACCAGAAAUCUUUAGUUAAUUUUUUUACCCAUAUAAUUUAAUUUCCAAAAUAUUAUUCAGGUAAUUAGGCAUUUCUAGAUAGAGUAAACUGCUAUAUACUCAGCAUAGUGAGCAGUUACUUUUUUCCCAUUUAGCGUGAUUAGGCAUAAUUACUGAUAAUUUCUGUUGAUAAUCUGUUUUGUACCUUAUGAAUCCAAACAUUAAUGCAACAUGUUGAGCUUCUUUACAUGUCCCAGUUGUCCACAUUGGCUCUUAGCAGAAGGUUGAUGUAUAUUGCCAGUACUAAGAAGGAUAAAGUUACUGGUCAGCAUUGCCCCAAUUUUGAGAAACUUUGAAAGCUCCUGAGUUUUGGGGAAGAGGUCAGUGGUUCAGGACCAGAUUUCAACAGGAAUGCAGCCUAUUUACACUAAGUCUAGUUGAGUAUCUGGGUCCAAAAAGAGAUCAAUUCCUAAAGAAACAGCCUACAGUUGGGGACUGGGAGUGAGGAGGCGGGGAGGAAGGCAGCGCAGUUCUGUGACUGUAAUGCAGAGGUGUUAUUAAUACCACUUGCCAAGGUGGGCAUUUCCAAGACUUCCUUCAAGAUGAGAUGGGAGGAGACCAGAAUAGGAUACACACAAGCCCCUGGAGAUCUGAGCCUUGGCAAAAACAAAGCGAGGAAUGACCUGAAGAUGCCAGGAGGGAGUGUGCCUAGGAGGGAGUCAGAGAGGCUUGUGGGGGAAAGGAGCAGCCUGUCUGUAUUCAGGUGUGGGGCAGCAGAGCUGGGAGUGGGGGGUGCCUGUGGAUAUCCUGGACAGCUGUUCUCCCAGGCUGCCAGGAGCGGGUGGCUUACUGACACUCAGAUGUCCAUUCUGACUGCUCACAUGGAUCUAGACAGUGCCAGAUGGCAACAGUAUUUCCUAUGAAGUUGCCGUAAGUGCAUGUUAGGCAAAUGGUAAAAUGUUAUACUAAGAUAUUAAUAUUUCAUAAUCUGGAAUAUAUGAGAUUGAUAAUAUGAAGUACACAUUUUGUUUCAUUUUCUUUGAACUAGCUUGGUUUAAAAGUACUCUUGUUGUGGCCAGGCACAGUGGCUUAUGCCUGUAAUUCCAGCACUUUGGGAGGCUGAGGUGGACAGAUCACUCGAGGCUAGGAGUUCAAGACCGGUCUGGCCAACACGGUGAAACUCAGUCUCUACCACAGAUACAAAAUUGGCGGGUGCCUGUAAUCUCAGCUACUCUGGAGGCUGAGGCAGGAGAAUCACUUGAACCCAGGAGGUAUAGGUUGCAGUGAGCUGAGAUCGCGCCACUGCACCCCAACCUGGGCUACAGAGCAAGACUCUGUCUCAAAAAAAAAAAAAAAAAAAAACAGUGGGGGAGAGUACUCUUUUAGCUUUUCGGAAUUACUUGAAGAUUCUCAGUGACGGUGCUUUUUCUCCACCCGCUUUCCAGUUUGUAUCAUUUUUUGCCAACUCUGGCAUUUUCUACGUAGUGUACUUUCUGUAACUAAAUUUGUUUUUUACGUUUAUGGCUGUGUAGCAGAAAAUUCAACAGUAAUUGUUUAAAGUUUGGUUUGAGCAAUUUGGGAAGAUAGCAGUUCCUAAAACAAGUUAGCAAUGUUCUUACCAUUUGGGAUGAAUAUCAGAGAUACAGGGAGACUGACUGUCAGACAUGUUGUCUUCAAGGCUCUUAGCAAAUACUCUGAUGUGAGCUCAGGUUAUUUCAUCUAUAAACUGGUGAUAGUAUCUGCCAAAUUGUUUAGUACAAAAGAAGCAUAGAUAGUACAUAGAUGGGGCAAAGGAAACUGUGGCUAGAGUGGGUCGGUGGGCAUGGUACCAUAAAAGUAGACCUCUACCUGUCUUUGCUGCAAAGUCUUCUGAGCUUUUAUUCAUGCAGCACCCCCUUCAUUUAUUCAACAGACAUUUGGAUGUGUAUAGUAUUCAAUUAUUUAUUCUUCCUUUCAAUUUGUAUGUAUAAGGGGUUGGGGAUUCCAAACAAAGAGUGUCCUCAAGAAGCUUCUGUUUGUUAGAGAGACAAUCAGACAAUUUUGCUGGAGCAGUUGGUACAGCAGAGUAAGGAUGUGGAGUCCACUGUGAGCUGAGGUGUGUAGGAAGCAUAGAGGACAAGAGGAGGGAAGGUGUCCCAGACACAGGAGAGAGCGCUGCCUUUCUUAGCUAUCCCAUAUGUCUCAGCCUCAGGGAAAAAAGUCACAGGACGGGUUGGUGGGAUCAUGCAAGGUUGUGUGUGCCAUACCAAAAGGGUGGUAAGCAGAGCCCUGCAAAAGUUUAGGCUGGGAAUGACAUGAUCAAGUGAGUGUCCAGCAGCAGCGUGGAGGAUGAGACUAGCCUGGAGGAGGGCGGGUCAUUUCAAAGGAUGCUGAGAUAACCCAGGAGAGUUAUUGAUGGUAAAUGUGCUGUAGGGCUCUGACUCUCUUUAGCUUCGAGACCUCAAGCAAGAUGCUUAACCUCUGCGCCUCAUUUUUCUUCAUGUGUAAAGUGAAGAUAAUAAUAGUACCAACUUCAAAAAAAGGUUAUGGAGUGGUUAGAAGUGAUGAUUAUGCAAUGCCUGGUAUGUAGCAGGCUUUAAGUAAAUAGCAAUAAUUAUUAUAAUGCCAGGUCUCAAAGGUCAUUCAAACCCAACUUAUUCAAAAUAAACCUUUUUUUUUCUUUUUUGGUGGCCUGCAAUAUCAGUGUUCUCCACCUCACUUUGUCAUCCUCCCAGACGUACCUCAUCACCAGCAACCUCAGCAUGAUCCUUGACAGGACCCUCUCCCUCCUGUUGUAUGGGCUUUAUCACCCAUCGCCGAUGAUUUUAUCCUCUAUGUAAAUCUGGAAUCCAUUCACUUCUCUCCAGUUCUGCCAUUACAACUGUCUUAGCCCAGAGGAUUACAUUCUGCCCUUAAAUGGUUGCUGGGUAUCUCCUCUCCAUUCCACCUCUCCCCGCUCCACCCCAUUCUCCACUUGGGAACCAGAGUGUGACGAUCUUCCAAAAACAGAAAUUAAUUACAUUGCUGCCAUAUUAAAGAAAGAAACUCCAGUGAUUUCCCAUUGCUUUAAAGAAAAAUAUCAACAUUUAUCUUACACUGUUGGUGGGACUGUAAACUAGUUCAACCAUUGUGGAAGAUAGUGUGAUGAUUCCUCAAGGAUCUAGAACUAGAAAUACCAUUUGACCCAGACAUCUCAUUACUGGGUAUAUACCCAGAGGAUUAUAAAUCAUGCUGCUGUAAAGACACAUGCACAUGUAUGUUUAUUGUGACACUAUUCACAAUAGCAAAGACUUGAAACUAACCCAGAUGUCCAUCAAUGAUAGACUGGCUUAAGAAAAUGUGGCACAUAUACACCGUGGAAUACUAUGCAGCCAGAAAAAAGGAUGAGUUCAUGUCCUUUGUAGGGACAUGGAUGAAGCUGGAAACCAUCAUUCUCAGCAAACUAUCGCAAGGAUGGAAAACCAAACACUGCAUGCUCUCACUCACAGGUGGGAAUUGAACAAUGAGAACACUUGGACACAGGGUGGGGAACAUCACACACCGGGGCCUGUCAUGGGGUAAGGGGAGGAGGGAGGGAUAGCAUUAGCAGAUAUACCUAAUGUAAAUGACAAGUUAAUGGGUGCAGCACACCAACAUGGCACAUGUAUACAUAUGUAACAAACCUGCACAUUGUGCACAUGUACCCUAGAACUUAAAGUAUCAAAAAAAAAAUAAUCCAAUACACAUCAAUUCUUUUUCAUCCAGUUGUUUUAUAUAUUUAAGCACAGAGAAACCCAAGCAAGGGCAUGUAACACACUUUACGUCAGUCUUCAGGGGGUGAGAUUGGAGGUGGGGCCAGUUGGUGGCUCUGAGCUGGGCUCUAGGACUAGACUCCUUGGGAUAUCUAGUUCUCACUUUCUAACUUUAUGGCCCUGGGCUUUUACUUUGCACUUCCCUAUGGAUAAUAACAGCAUGAAAACACUUAGGAAGUACCUAGCAUCCAGUAAAUACUAUAUAAAUGGUAUGCUGCUAUUACUUCUUUUCCUAUUGUUGAGUUGUUGCAGUAAACAUACUUUACUUUUACAGCCCCUUAAAAAUUUUAAGAGAAAAUUUUAAAGGAAGAGAGAUGGAAGAGUCCAAGGAAGUCUCAGUGAAAUCUCAUUGUUGCCUGCAAGUCUCUGUGAUAGUCCCCUGCCUAUUCUGCAGCUUCAUCAUGUGCUGCUUUUCUUCCCCUUUCUUUCUGGACCCGAGUCAUGCCAGUCUUCUCUCAAUUCCUGCAGCCUGACCUCUGCUCAUCUUUCAGGUCUCAGGUCAAAGUUACUUCCCUGGGAAGCUUUGACCUGGGUCUCUUAGACAAAGUCUGAUUCCCAUAAUCUCACAGCACUUUUUCUCUAGAGCGUGGAUCCUAGUUAUAAUUACAUACUUCUUUGAGUGAUUGUUUAAUAACUGACACCCAUCACUUGUCAAGAAUCUCUAAGAGGCCAUGACUGUCCACUUUGCUCAUCAUUAUAGCCCUCAGGGCCUAGCACAGCAGUUUGCCUAAAUAAGUAGGAAAAGGGCAUCCCACAGAACUGGGAGUAAGGCCAGGUUUGGAGUAGAGAACAUAAGCUCCAUGAGGACAUGCAAGAAGUGCCACUGGAGAACAGGGGAACUGCUGUGUUCUGAAGGAAGGAUUUUGAAUUGUGUCCAGGUAUUUUAGGAGCUAGUGAGAGAUUUUAGCCAAGGCCAUGAUUAUAGGAUUAGAUAGCAUUUUAGAGUGGUCACUCCAGCACCAGUGUGGUGGAUGGGUGGAAUACAGGGUCAGAACUUAUACAACAGGGAUGGAGCAGCUGGAACAGCUUCAGGAAACAUUCGGAUGGAAGGACUAAUGGUACUAUGUGUGGAGUGGAUGUGAAGAGAUGCCAUGAUGAUAAAGAUGACUUCCGCGUUCCCGGUUUAUAUUACUUUCUGGAUUUUGACUUUCAUUUGGGAAGUUAAGGAACAGAGAGUGAAGAUCAGAUUUAGAGAGAAUACUACGAAAUUAGAUUUGUAUAUGUUAAACACCUGCAAGGCAUCGUAGAGGAAUUGUCCAGUGGAGGCAGGCAUAAGGUGGUCUGGGCUAGGAAGAGAUUUAGAAGACACAGGUCUGCACAAAGUGGAUGCUGUAGGUGUGAAUGAGGUGGUCCAGACAGCAGUCCUUCCCAUAGGUCCAGCCCAAACCCAUCUUCUGUAAAGAAAAUUUCAGUCUAUAAGGAUUCCACAUUUUCUGCCUGCAAGUGCUUUUUUAUAUUCAGAAGUUUUUCUUAGAGGCCAGCAGGGAAGCUGUAAUAUACAGAAAUAUCUGCCCUCAGACAUUUCCCUGCAUAGUAGGACAGUGUUUUCACAUAGUCGUUCUGCAAGAAUCAUGGUAGGUGUGCUUCUUCCAGGCACUUAUCAGUGGGCGGUGGACCUGGCAUUCAUAUCAGCAAGGGAAGUGGAAGCAAAGGUCAAUAUGAAAUAAAUAUUCAUGGUUUCAUGUUAAAAACAAAUUAAGAAGGGUGAAACCAGUAUAUCAGUCAUACUUCUCCAGAGAAACAGAACCAGUUGGCAGCAGAGUUGGAGGAUAGGGGGUGGUAUUUAUAGAUAGAGGGAGGGAGAUUUACUUUAAGGAAUUGGUUCACACAGUUAUAGAGGUACAAGUCCAAAGUGCUGGAUAGAGACCUAGCAGGCUGGAGACCUGGUAAAGAGCUGCAGUUUGGGACCAAGGGCAGUCUCCUGGCAGGAUUCCUCCUUUUUUUCUUUUUUAAGGCCUUCAGCUGGUUGGAUGAGCCCCUCGCACAUUAUAGAGGGAGUCUGCUUUACUCAAAGUCUACUGAUGUAAAAUGUUAAUCCUGUCCAAAAAUAGAACUUCACAGAGACAUCUAGAAUAGUGUUUGACCAGAUAUCUGUAUACCGUGAUCAAACCAAGUUGACACAACAUUAACCAUCACACUCAGUAAGCUGCCCUGUCUGCUCCAGGAAAGCUCUGCAAUGCUGCAGGUCUAGAAAAGAUGGCCUCCAUGUGAGGUUCAGGCUUUAGUCUGAUUAUCUCGAGCUUAAAUGUCAAGUGUCCAAAACAUCCAAAAUUUCAAGACCUUAAAGAACCAAAGGCCAUUGCUUGUUAAGGAGCUUUGCUGUUGCUUUAAGGGUGUUUAAUGCAUCAUGGUUUUUUCAUUUUGUCUCACAGUUUGUAUUACAAAACUAAAAACUCAUACACUCAACACACAGAAAAUAAGCAUUUCAUGGUUCUUUUCCAUUUUACAGAUGAGGAAACGGGUUGAGCCAGUGUUAGGUUCCAUGCCAAAUUGAGGACCAUUAAGUGGCUAGUUUGAACCUAGGUCUUCUCACUGUAAAUUGAGCCCUUCCUGUCCCUCCCUGCCAUGCCCCCAAACACCUUAUUUCUAAAAGAGAAGGAAGGGAGAGAGAAAAACAGAGACAGACUAUGGGAAUGAAUAUUUACAGAACUCCUACUUGAAUUCACGGUAGGGGAAAUAAAAAUAAAUUUACCAGAUUAUAUGCCUAACUUGAUCCCUCUGGGGUUGUAGGUAUUUCAAGCUACUUGGAAAUUAGAGGAAUUUAAGUUUGCAGUCCAUUCCUUCCUCCGUCUGCAUUUUUUGUAUUUGUGGAUGAGUAAGUAUUGAAACUCUGAAGAAACCACCUCUUUCACUCACUCAGGUCACCUCCUCGCUGCCCCAUGCCUUUGAGAGGGUGUUUUCACAGUCAUUGAGUCUGUCGGGUUUGGGUCUUGUGGUAUGCCUCCUUCCAGUUUGUUUGGUUAGUUAGCGAAUGUGUUUUGCAUUCAACCAAGGAAGUUCAAAAUACUGUCUCUGAGAGAGCCGGUUAAGGUAGAAAUGCUGUCCAAGUUACGAGUGGCAGACUGGCUGAGUUCUCCGGGCGAUGAUUGAGAAAACCACCCACUAAUUUUAGGCUGGAAGAGCUUGCAGCACAAAUUGAGUUUUGAGUAGAAAACAAGGUCUUACUGAGAUAUCCUAUAGCCAUUGGAAACACCUUCUGGCUCCUUAGCUCUUGGCCACUGUGAAAGUUCGUAUCACUUACUCAUUGUCAUAUCAAAUGUGGUAAAGAUCUUAGUUUUGAAUAUUCUGCAUUCUGCCUAAGAUCAUUUAGAUCUCAAAGGUAAUGGCAGCAGAGCUUGUCCUUCUUUCCUAUGACUAAUGCAGAUGGGAAGCCGUAAGCCUCAGGCAGCAGUCUCACUUUUAAGUGGAUAAGCCGGGUAAUAGCGCACAGAAUUACCGAGUUAUCAGUUUCAAGCUUGUGGGCCAUAUACUAAAUCGUAGUGUCCUAAAAUGUGUAUUCACUCACCCCACUUACGUACAUAUUGUAACUUUUCAAAGAAUUGUCCUGGCUUCAUCAGAUAGUUUCAUCUGCUUUGUUUUGCCAGGAUGACGUUUAAGUGUGUGGCCAAAGCUCCAAUUGGUCUUUCACAAGAAAAUUGCAUAUGGCUCUGUUAGUCCCAAUUCUGGCACCAUUUCAAACCUUCUGGAGCCAUAACCAGGCCAUUAAAAAGUAAAUAUUUUCCAGGAAUUGAUUUCCCAAUGUAUUUGUGCCUUGAAUAUACAGGUGCCCAUGUCUAAUUCUGUAUGGUUUUGAAUAUCUCCCUAGAGUCUCUCAUUGGGUUUUCACAACAAAUCUGCAGUUGGUAGAAGAGCUGAUGUUAUAAAAUAAGCAAAAACAGAGGAAUGGCAUUUACUUAAGGACCCCUAGACUGUAUAGUUUUAGCAGUCACCAUUUUCUGUCACCUACUUUGAGCCAGGAAUUGUGCUGUUUUACAGACAGCCACUAAUAUUAUUUAAUCCUCGUAACAACCUGUGAAGUCAGGAAGGUAAGUUUCAGGGUAGUUUUAAGUUUUCAAGUAGUUUUAGUUUUACCGAAGGGCUGGUAAGUGGAGCCCAUCUGGUCUAAGGCCCAUGCUUGUUCCGAUUCAAGCUGCACUUCAUUUCAGGUUGAUACUGUUAAGUUCAGUGGCUGUUUAUGAUCCAUAUUUAACUUUUCAUCCAUCAGAGUGUUUGAGUGGGGAAUAAAUAGGUCAGAACUGAUGUAGAUUUAACUUUUGUUGGUGCCCAGCCUCGCUAUAUGCAGACUUCAAUAAUUGUAUAAAUCCCUGUAUUUACAUUUUUAUGACAAUUGAGAUGUUUCAAUCCAGAAGAAAGUACAGCAUGAGGGAAUUAAGAUGUUUAAAUUUGGUAAGUACUUAUAGAGCACCAGUAUUUGCUGGGCACUGUGAUUGCUGCUUUCAUAUAUACUGUAUGAUUUUUUUUUUUUUUUUUUUUUGAGACGGAGUCUCGCUCUGUUGCCCAGGCUGGAGUGCAGUGGCGCGAUCUUCGCUCACUGCAAGCUCCACCUCCCGGGUUCACGCCAUUCUCCUGCCUCAGCAUCCCGAGUAGCUGGGACCACAGGCACCCACCACCACGGCCGGCUAAUUUUUUGUAUUUUUAGUAGAGAUAGGGUUUCACCGUUUUAGCCAGGAUGGUCUCGAUCUCCUGACCUCAUGAUCCGCCCGUCUCGGCCUCCCAAAGUGCUAGGAUUACAGGUGUGAGCCACCGUGCCCGGCCUACUGUAUGGUUUUUAUAACAUCCCGGCAGGCCUUAAUUAUUGUUUGUUUACAGAUAACGAAACCGAUCCUCAAAAAAGAAUACAUUACUUGGGGAAGGGCACACAGCUAAUAAUAAAUAGAGCUGGACACAAACUAGCGUCUUUGAACCUCAUGCCCAUUACUCUUUCUGGUAGUGUCAGCGUUCGCUGCUUACAGUGCACUCCGUUGCUCCCAUGGUCACUCUGCUCUUCCACAGCCCACCAUCAGCCCAACCCAUUGCUUGCCAUUUGCAUCCCUCACUUGUGAACUUCAGAUCAAUUAAGCAUCAACCCAGAAAGCAUUUCCUGAAUUGCAACUAGAAUUGUCUACAGGAAAUCAUGCAUCUAAAGAAGGUAUUAUAUUAUGCAGUCAUUAGCAUCUUGUUUAGAAACCUGUGCUUUUCAGAAUUAAUUUCACAGAAAGCAGUGGAGUUAUCUAUCAAGCAUUUCUGAGAAAUAAAUACAAGAGAUGGAUACAUGUAGUUCAAAUCAGGACAACUCAUUAAAUCUGCAGUGGGUAUUGAAGGAGUCCUGAGGUAAUUGAACAUAGUAAUUGCAUUGCUCUGUCCAAAGGGUUUCACUGACACCUGUUUUGUUUGUGUUUUGCUGGAGCCCAUAAUUGCAGAAAUAUUCUCCCAUGGUGAUUAGCUCCCAGUUCAAAAUGGACUGUUUCAUUAAAGGUAACUCCAUAAUGAGACCAGUAAGGACCCAAGCUGUGUCCUUUAACGAGAGUAAUUCCCUCUUCACUUGCAGCUUGACCAUGUGCACACAGAACCGUGUGAGUCAAAGCCUCCAACUUAAGGCCUGUUUGAACUGCAAGAAAAGAGGAGGGUGAAUUACAUUGCCUUUAAGGUCUGUUCCAGCGUUAGCAUUCUAUGAUUCUUUGGAAUAUUCGCCAAAUAGAAGUUCAAAAAUUGAUUCAGCUUUCACACUGAGAGAGAAGAAUGCCCACAAUUGAAUAAAAGAUUAGAGGCUGUAGAGAGGAAAUCGUUGCCUUGAGUGAGUUCUUUUAUUGGAAAUCAGCCUUGGACUACUGGACAGGAAAUUAAGUUCUUGCCUGGGUCAUUAAUCAUUGUGCCGAUUUGAAAAUUGGCAGUGGGGGAAGGUGGCUAUAUUUGAGGAGGAAGGAAGGAGUGGGCGGAAAGAGCGGUCCUCAAAGCUCCCAGUCUGAGUGGGCAUUCGCCAGCAAAGAGAGGGUAGUAUCAGCCACCUCCUUCUGGCAGAGGUGUCUAGAUAUUUUUGUCAACUCUCCUGAGGGUGCCCACAUAUCUCGUACCCAAACCUGUUUCCCACUUCUACCAAGAAGAGGGAAAUGGAAUCAUGGGAUUUUCACUGGGUAAGGGCAGAGAAGUGAUCUAUCGGAGGUUGUAUUUCUGUGUUUAGCUCAAGAGAGGUAGACAAAAUUAGGAUAUCCUUAAUUUUUGUCAAAGUUAACAUUGACAAGAAACCUUUAAAACCAGCAAAAACACAGGGAAUAGGUUAUGCCGUGUCAGGACUGCCUGUGCCCCUCAAAAGUACACCAUCUUUUACUAUCUCCUGUUCCUCCGCUUCCAUGUGGAACCCCACUCGGGGGAAAUAUCUUUUGCUGCAUAAAGCCGGAGCCUCCCUCUGCAUCUGUUCCUUGGACUAGAAAAAUAUUAAGACCCUCCUGGCUUUCGCUUGUCCAUCCUCCCCCCACUCCCUGUGACUGUUUAAGAGUAUUUGCACUUUCCUAUUUUUCCUGUAAGGUGAGAAGUUUUGGUAAAUAAAAACUUGGCAGCAGGUUUUAUUUCCACAAAAAUAACAAUCUUGACAUCUCGGGGUGUCGUGUGUUUUAAAGCUGUUGCCGGUAGAAUCUAAAUAUACCUCUGGGCUUUCUCGUCGCACAUCCGAACUGCCUGGAAAAUGUGCCCCCCUCGGGGUGUGAUUAAGUCUUCUAUAAAGCUCUCUCUUCUCCUAUAGAUUUUUCUGAUGGGAAAGUGGCUAAGUUAGAUUGGGAAUUGAAGUAUCUGGCUGGGUUACAGUUUGUGUGGGUUUCUGCUCUUUCUCUCUCUCGGGACACCAGCUUCUUUCCGACUGCAAUGUCACAAUGUUCCUAACUGCUCAGUGCACAAUAUGGUCUCAGCAUCCCUGACAGAUCCUGCCCUGAAUCAUCCUCCGGAGCCAUCUAGGGGCUGGCCUGUGUGGUUGUGGCUUUCCUGCUUAGGUGGAACAAAUAGACUUCUCUCUUCACUCUGCGGACCGCACACCGGCCUGUGUAGCGACCUGAGUCUUGACUCCAUGCUGGACACAGCUGCUCCUGCUCCCAUUGUUGACACCAAUGAUAAGCACCUAGAGGUUAUUUCCAAAACUGAGGAGGAAAAAAAAUACCAAAUGCAAUCAGGUUGAGCGUCAUUGUCAGCCCAGGAAGAGCAUUCAGAGCAGCUAAUGUUGUAGAGGAUGAGAUCUAUUGCCAUGGAGCCACCUCUUCACAGGAAAUCACACAGCCUUGCAGCAUUGGAGGCUCCUUUGAAUUAAAAAGAGUGGGUGAGGUUUCCACUUUAUUGGAGUUUGUAUACUGGCUCAGGAAGUUAUACAAACUACUCAAGAACUCCUGUAGUUCUGACUUGGAAUACUGGAUUGCAGCAGUGCCUACAAGGGGCCUCAAUCUUCUCUUUUGGCACUUGCCCUUGAAACUUGGCUUCUGACAUAACAGCUUCUCACCAUCAGACCCAUGGUCUUUCCCUUGUCUGCUCCUUGGCCCUCUGUAGCCCCAGACACUAGUGAGAACUCUCCUUGGGACUCCUCUUCCCACUCUCCCUAACAUUCCAUUCUCCCAGCUUUCUGUCUGCUGUUCAUUUUCUCUUUUUUUGGUCCAUCCACUAUGUUGACGUGAAGAUUCAGUGCCUGUUCCCCCUCCCCCUCUCCACUCCCCUUCCUUGUCUCUCUUCCACCUCCUCCUCCUCCUCUAUCCCUCUUCUUCCCUCCUCUUAAUGUCUCUCUCUUUCUUUUCCCUCUCAUCAUCUCCACAGAAAACCUAACCCUCCUGGCUUCCCUGUCAUCUCCUGUAGGUCUCACUAUUUAAUCAACUCCCAUUCCAAAGUUCAGCAGCCUACUGAAUACAUUUCUACUUUUUUAUUUUAUCAUCAUCUCAGCCUCAGCUUCUCUAAAGAAAAAAAAAAAAUUCUCCCCUAACGGCACCCUCCUCUCCUCUCCUGUGUCUAUUUUUGUCAUUGUCAUUUCAAUCCAUGUCCUAGGCCACUAUAUUGGCCACUGAUACUCUCUCUCUGUCAUGCCAUCGUUUUCAGGAAAGAGUCCACACAGGCUUCUGGGGCACAGACAGGAGGGACCAGCUUUAAGAGCUUAGAAACAACAGGUUCCAUCUCUGAAGCCUCAAGUGCCAAGCACUGCACUGAACUCUUCUCUAGGUUUACUACGUUUAAUCCCGACAGUGUCCCGUCAGAUGGUGUGGUAGGAGACACAGCAGGGACAGUGUGGUGGGCUUGGUGAUAGGCAGGGAGGCUGAAGGAGAGUGGGACUCAGCUACUGAAGUGCUGAGAGCAGAGGACUGAUAGGAUUGAACUGCUGCCUCCACAGCCCUCCUUGUCCAGCUGCCACGCUGCACUUACAGUUCCUCAGGUAGAAGGAAGGCCACACCAGUGCCAAAUGCCCCUACCAAUGACAGCUUCUGCAUGCCACCCUUCCGUAGCACUUAACUGCUGUGUCAAUUAAAUCUUAGCUGCAAAACUGGUUGUAGAAAGUGUAUAUCUCCAACCCCCCCAUGUGAGCAUGGGGGCUGGGCUGCGUCUCUGGUGUGUUACAUGGCGUGCCUCUGUGCAGUAAACACCGCAUCCACUGAGCGAAUGAACACCAGCAUUCAGGACCUCAGACCCAAGCUGCUCAGAGCACAAUGCGCUCUUCCCGGCCCCGCCAUUACUCUCUUAAAACCUGGUAGGCAAAGACUACACUAAGCCAUGUAUUUCUCACUCCUCUGAGCAGAGCCAAAACUGUAUCCCAAAGGAAGGCACACCAGAAAGUCUUAGCACUCCAAAAAGGGAGGAUAAAAGAGGAAGAGGACGCAAGUCCCCAACCACAAAUGCCCCAAGUGAGUUGCCUCUGUCAAGCAUCCUAGAUGAUACUCUCUUCACCCUUCCUGUACGAAAGGACACAGUCAGUUCUGUGAUGUCUACAAGGGAGGAGGGAAAAGACCAAUGCCUUUUCCCGUCCCCUGGGUCACCAGCCCUGUCAGUCUGUCCCUGCCGUGCGUCCUUCCCACCCAUGGCUCUGCCUGCGCCCAGAUGUUGUCACCACUCGCAGUGUUUCUCUCCUCACUCUUUCCCCUUCACCUUCUUUUAAUGACCCAAAGCCCAACCCACCCCCAGACCUCUCUCAUAUCCCAGUUUCUUCUCUGUUCUAACAAUACAAUUGUGACCUGUCCCUCCUCUUAUUAUUUAGGCCAGGAGUUCUCAAAGGGGAACCUUGUCACCUGGGAACUUGUUAUAGAUGCGUUCUUGAUCCCCAUCCGACACCUUCUGAAUCAGACACGGGCAAUUCAAGCUGCUGGAACAAGACCGAGAUAUAAAGGAGCCAGUGCAAUAUUUCAACAGUGUGGAGGAGGUGGCUAAGGCAUUUCCUGAACGCGUGUACGUCAUGGAGGAUAUCACAUUCAACGUGAAGGUUGCUUCAGGUGAAUGCAAUGAAGACACUGAAGUUUACAACAUCACCCUGUGUACUGGGGAUGAACUCACUCUAAUGGGGCAGGCAGAAAUCCUUUAUGCAAAGACAUUCAAGGAAAAGUCACGACUCAACACAAUCUUCAAAAAGAUUGGGAAGCUCAAUUCCAUCAGCAAGCUGGGAAAAGGCAAAAUGCCGUGCCUCAUUUGUAUGAAUCACCGGACCAACGAAAGCAUUAGCCUUCCAUUCCAGUGCAAGGGCAGAUUUAGCACCCGAAGUCCCCUGGAACUUCAGAUGCAAGAGGGCGAACACACCAUCCGCAACAUUGUGGAGAAAACCAGGCUUCCUGUGAAUGUGACUGUGCCAAGCCCUCCACCGAGAAACCCAUACGACCUCCACUUCAUCCGUGAGGGGCACCGCUAUAAGUUUGUGAACAUCCAGACCAAGACGGUGGUGGUUUGCUGUGUGCUGCGGAACAACAAGAUCCUCCCCAUGCACUUUCCUUUGCACUUGACUGUCCCCAAGUUCAGCCUCCCAGAACACCUGGUGAAGGGAGAGAGCUGGCCCGAAACCCUGGUCCAUCACUGGCUAGGUAUCUGCCAAGAACAGUUCGACAUCGAUGAGUAUUCACGGGCUGUCCGUGAUGUGAAAACCGACUGGAAUGAAGAAUGCAAGAGCCCCAAGAAGGGUCGGUGCUCUGGCCACAACCACGUGCCCAAUUCGCUCAGCUACGCCCGCGAUGAGCUCACCCAGUCCUUCCACCGACUCUCGGUCUGUGUGUAUGGCAACAAUCUCCAUGGCAACAGUGAGGUGAACCUUCAUGGUUGCAGGGACCUGGGGGGAGAUUGGGCUCCCUUUCCUCAUGACAUCCUGCCCUAUCAGGACUCUGGAGAUAGUGGGAGCGACUACCUUUUCCCAGAAGCUAGUGAAGAAUCAGCAGGCAUCCCGGGAAAGUCAGAACUUCCCUACGAAGAGCUGUGGCUGGAGGAAGGCAAGCCCAGCCAUCAGCCUCUCACUCGCUCUCUGAGCGAGAAGAACAGAUGUGAUCAGUUUAGAGGUUCUGUCCGAUCCAAAUGUGCGACUUCUCCUCUUCCCAUCCCUGGGACUCUGGGAGCAGCAGUGAAGUCUUCAGAUACUGCCCUACCUCCACCUCCAGUGCCUCCCAAAUCUGAAGCCGUCAGAGAAGAAUGCCGGCUCCUGAACGCCCCACCUGUUCCACCCCGAAGCGCAAAGCCUUUGUCCACCAGUCCCUCCAUCCCUCCUCGCACAGUCAAGCCAGCGCGGCAACAGACUCGCUCUCCCAGCCCCACCUUGUCCUACUAUUCUUCAGGGCUACACAACAUCAGCGUCACUAAAACUGACACAAAUCCUUCUGAAAGCACUCCUGUUUCCUGCUAUCCAUGUAACCGAGUGAAAACUGAUUCUGUGGACCUGAAAUCCCCGUUUGGAAGUCCUUCUGCUGAAGCUGUGUCCUCUCGGCUCUCAUGGCCUAACCAUUAUUCAGGAGCAUCAGAAAGCCAGACCAGGAGUGACUUCCUGCUGGAUCCAAGCAGGAGUUAUAGUUACCCUAGACAAAAGACGCCAGGCACACCAAAGAGAAACUGCCCAGCACCUUUUGAUUUUGAUGGCUGUGAGCUCCUGGCCAGCCCCACUAGCCCAGUCACUGCAGAAUUCAGUAGCAGCGUCUCUGGUUGUCCCAAGUCAGCCAGCUACUCUCUGGAGAGCACAGAUGUGAAAUCUCUUGCAGCUGGUGUGACAAAGCAGAGUACGUCAUGCCCUGCCUUACCCCCCAGGGCUCCAAAACUAGUGGAAGAGAAGGUCGCCUCCGAAACAUCUCCUUUGCCUCUGAAAAUUGAUGGUGCUGAGGAAGACCCCAAGUCUGGGUCACCAGAUCUCUCGGAGGACCAGUAUUUUGUUAAAAAGGGCAUGCAGGACAUCUUCUCUGCCUCCUACCCUUUCUCAUCUCCGCUCCAUCUCCAGCUGGCCCCCAGAUCCUGUGGCGACGGUUCCCCAUGGCAGCCACCUGCUGACCUAUCAGGACUCUCUAUAGAGGAAGUGUCCAAGUCACUACGGUUCAUUGGUUUGUCCGAAGAUGUCAUAUCAUUCUUUGUUACUGAAAAGAUUGAUGGGAACCUGCUUGUUCAGCUAACGGAAGAAAUCCUCUCAGAGGAUUUCAAAUUGAGCAAAUUGCAGGUGAAGAAGAUAAUGCAAUUCAUUAAUGGCUGGAGGCCCAAAAUAUAGCCAAAUAACCCCCGGCCAGCAUGGAACAAAACUGAUCAAUGCGUGUGCUAGAAGGGGUGGGCUGGGACACAAUUUCAUGUUUUUGCACUAAAAACCUUCUCUGUAAAUAGGGAUAAGAGAAACUCUUACUAUGCAGAUUACGUUUUUGAAUGGUGAACAGGCUAUUUUGUACAUCAAUAAAAAUGCUGUACAGAACACUUGGAGGUGUGCCUUGUACGUCACUCAACAAACACUCAGCAGCUGCUAAAAGAAAAAAAGGCAUGUGCAGAGAAAUCAUUCUUACCCAAGUAGGUUUAUGUGAGAAGGUAUGAUAUUUAUUACAAAAUAGCCAAAGCUGGAAGACAUAAAAAUCUUUAAAAAAAAAAAAAAAACACUUUUGAACAAGUCCCUUCUUUCAGGAGGGUUGACUUUAGACAAUUAACUGUGUUCUGUGCUCUGUCAUUCAGAUUGCUUCUUGCUAAUUGUUUUACUCUUGUGCCUGAAAAUGUUAGUGAUACGAAUUGACACUUUAAUGUUGUAUGCUUGGUGGGGAUCUUUUUAUCACAAGGCAUUUUCCAAGAGUCAUAUGUUGAUAAAGGGAUAUAUGUUGUCCUUAGAAAUCACACAAAUCAUGACCACAAUAAUUUAUCUGUAACUGCUGCUAAUUUUAUUGAGCAGAGAAAAAAGAAUAUACAUAUAUAAACAUGUAUAGGUGCAUACACAAUACACCCGGAUAUGUUUUACACAUAAUUUUGAUUCUGAUAUUUUAGAUAACAUCUGUUCACUUUUAAACAAUCUGUUGAGGUUUUGGGACUGUUAUCUACAUUGAUUCUCUUAGGAAUAGUGGACAGAAUGACUCCAAAGAUUCUCAGAACCCUGUCUCUUGAAGCUCAAUCUUAUUUGGGUUCAUCACUGAAAACUUAGAACAAAUCAGUAAAGAAUCCUGUAUUGAAGAAUUAAGUUUGAGUUUAAGCCCACUCACCGCAGGGCUGGUUUUUGCAUGUAAUACUCCCAUGAUGUCUGGGGAAAUGACAGUUUCUGUUGAAUUAUAAUUCUCCGGUUUAAGGGUCUCCUUCCCCUGGUGUCUGAUGGUGAGAGGUCUGAAGAGCAUUUGUCAGAGUACAUUAGGCAUUCUCAACCUACUUCAUGCUUUACGAGAGCUGAGAAAUCAGACGCACCGGCCUUUAUUAUUAUAUAUGCUACAUCUGUUGAGUAUUUUUAAAAUACCAAUAAGAGGACUUGUUUAUUUCAUAAACCACUUCUUCCCUCUCUUUCAAAGAAAAUACAUUAUUACCAUACUUUUACAUUAGUCUGAGAAUUUUUGCUAAAUAUGAUUAAGUAUUCCAAAAUAUAAUGGCGUCAUUAUUCUUGACUUUUUUAGAGAAUAUACAUCUUAAGACUGUAUUAGUUCUCAGAGCAAGGCAUCAUCUACUCCCCUGCACCUGAGAGUCUGGCCCCAGAUUCCAGAUGUGCGGACAGCCCAUGACCGAGGUGCACACAGUGCCCUCUUGAAUAGGAAGGUCAGCCAGUGAGGCGGCAGCAUAACUUGCAGGAUGGACUUAUAUCUUACCAUCUCUUCCUGCUACCAAAAUAAAAAAAUAAAUUGAAAGACAAGACCCACCAGUCUAGUUUUGUAGACCUGUGAAAUGUGUCUUUAUUUCUUGGCAUUAGAAGAAAGAUAUUUUUAAUCCAUAUCGUGGUUUUAGAGUUGAAGUGAAUUGAUACCCAAUUUUCCAUCUUAGAUCUCCUUUAUCAAAAAAAAAAGCAUUUUUUUUCUCCUAACGUGUCUCCCAAAAUGUAAAUACUAUAGGCAAAAAGAGUACCCUGUAAAAUUCUCACACUGGAGCACCUCUUCAAAAGUCACAGAUAACUCAAUGAGGAAGUGCUGGUACUGCACUCACAGGACAUGAGACCUAUGAAGCUUUCGUGUUUUGAAAGCAUCCUUCUGUGUGAGGGGGACUGCCUCCCUUAGUAAAGUAAACCUCUCAGAACUUCUUUUUAAAAUAAAAACAGACAAGAUGCAGUUACUAAGCUGCAAGUUUUCAUUGGCAAACCUAGCUGAAUCCGUUUUAAAAUACUUAGCACUCGGACACAAUUCUCAAACUCAGGAAGAAGGAACAGGGUUGGUUUGGGUUUACUAUAAAGGUUGCCUCACAUAAACAACUGACUCCUUUUAGCGUUUUUUUUCUUUUUGUAAAAACUUUACACAAAAUAGGGUUUUAAAUUCUUUUUGCUUGUUUUGGACUUGGUGUAUUUUUGUCAAGUUUAUAUUGAUUGGCAACGCAGAGACUCCUUGAGGGCAGGGACUGUGGCCUUUGAUUCACUUAUGCUACAGUCUAGUAUCACUACAGUGCUGAGUAAAAGACACAGCCCCUGCCCUCUUGGAGAUCAUAUUGUUUAUAUUUGAAAUCUCAGUUGCUAAGAGUAUGUAUGUGUGAGUAAGAAAGACGUGAAGUCCUAUGGGCAGCUGGGUAUAUGGAGAAUUACGUGUGUCCUGUCUUUAAAACGUCAGCCUCUAUUAAGGGGUACAGAACACCCCAAGAUCACUAAAACUUGGAAUGUGUUGGAGGCAGAAAGUAUCUCUCUCAUUGCCUAGUGUUGUUGUUUUUUUGUUUUUUGUUUUUUGUUUUUUUUACUGACCUGGAAUUCUUUUAAUUGUAAUAAAUAUCUUCUGUCACAAAUAAAUGCCACAAAUAAAUGAAAUUGCCAUUCCUAAGCUGAGCACCUGUCUGUGAAGGACCUUGGUGUCCUGACUGGACAGAGCAUUCAUAGCUCCAAGAGAAUCAUGACAAGAUAUGCAAAGCAGGGAUAAUAAGGAGAAAGCCCUUCCCUUUCGAGAAGCCCUUCCCUUUCACAGCCCUUCCCUGCGAUUCUGCAGUGAAAAGUGAUGCCCAGAGAUCCACACACAGAACCCUUCUAACCAGCCAGGUCAAGACUUAUCAUCUUAUCUCCUCUGGCAGGUCCCCUGUAAUCAAAAGAGAGGAAGUGUCUAUCUAAACAAGACCCUUUUGGGUCCUUAGAUUCAUGGCAAAAAUCAUCAUGGCCCCCAUCAGAAAAGAAAAUCAGCAAUAAACCAAGCCAAGCAACUAAAAUGUAUAAUGUGGACCUGACUCAUGUUGGGAGGCAGAAUUCAGACACUCACAGAUCAAUCUUGCAAGUUUUCUCUUCUUUAAGUUGAGCUGCUCAACUUUAUGAACUGUGAAAUUUACUUACAUUCUUUCAACCCACAUAUAUCAUUGCAGUUUAUGAAGUUGCAGUGAACUGCCCAUUCAGCUAAAUUGCAGUGUUUAUUCUUGUCUCAUGUCGAAAUACAACAAUCUUAUGGGAAAUAUUAUGACAGUCCGUUCCAACUGUUCUCAGACACAUGCAUAAACAGUCUCUGCUCACAUUCCACAGCCACCUGCAUGUUAUCCAUACAGCUCCCUGAGAAGUCCAGGGAUGGGAGGUGGGGUGUGGAAGGAUGGAGGGUCCUUCAUUUUCUAAACACUUUGUAUAAGUCACUACUCAUCGUGCCUAGCAAGUAUAAGAUUAACAUUUUGAAUAACAAACUGGAAAACAAAUAAUCCUUCAAAGAACCUAGCGAACUGUUCAAAGGAAAUUUUAAUUUCAGUCUACCAGAAAAGUUAAAUCUGUUGUUGGACGUAGGGGGCUUUCAGAAACAUGCCUCUUAUAUCAAUUUCCACUAUCUUUCAAGUUACCUAAAGGCACCAGGCUGCUUGAGCAAGAAGAAUAAAAGGCCUAGAGUGCAAAUUAUGUGAAGUAGAGUUUUUAGAUUGUGGGAUUGUAAUAAUACGGGAUUCUCAUGGUUACAUCAUGUUAAAUCACACUGUUCAGUCUUUAAAACUUGGUGUUUUAAAAUUUGUCUCAUUGUGAUAGCCAGAAACAAGGAAUAAACGUGAUUUCAGUUUAAACUAUAUACAAAUAUCUUCUGUAAUUUUGCUGCUCUAAUUUUUAGGCUAUAAAUUUUGUAAUAGAGCUUAUCAGAUCGCAAAUUUCCUUUGUUUACAAUCUCAUGUAGUAGGGCUCAGAUAAUUUCUUAGCUAUAAACCUUUUCUCCCACUCUCAUAUUGUUUCAUUUAAAAUAUUUAAGCUAAGCCUAAAAAUUGAAAUCAGUUAAGAAUUUGGAGAGUUUAUCUUAAAUGGAAAUGGUGUAUUCUUUUCAAAGAAUUUUGUAACCAUCUUUACAGUUUCUUUGCUUGGAAAACUUGGGUUGUUAACUACCAGUUAACAAUGGCAUUACUUUCCAAAACGUUAUCUAAUGGGCCCAAUGUGUACCUCAAGAUAAACACAGUAUGUUAUGUCUAAAAAUUUCCUUGUCUGUUGAUUUAAAUGGUUCUGAAAUGUCUGUAAUAAAGAAAUUUUCAAAGUUG